GAGGCAUUUGCUGGUGACAAGAGCGUUCCAUGCAGCACGGUGCUCUCCAAGUUCCCACCCCGCACCUCGGGGACUGAUGGGCAUAUAGGGAGCGGGAGGCUGGCCCCCAUCCUGUGACUGGUCCUGAGAGGGUGAAGGGAGCAGGGAAGAGCCACAGGCCAGGACAGCGGCCACCCGCUGGCAUCUUCUCUUGAGACAGCAUUCCUUGCCAUAUCAGCCUCUCAGGGAAGGGAAGGGAAACGGGGUGACGAGUAUUUACAAGCCGAAAGGUGCGGACCUGAUGCUCAGGGAGCCCACGACUUUGCCUAGAGUCACACAGCAAAGGGUCUGAAGCUCAUGGGAGCCCCGGUGAAGCUGACAGUGUCUCAGGGGCAGCCGGUGAAGCUCAACUGCAGUGUGGAGGGGAUGGAGGAGCCUGACAUCCAGUGGGUGAAGGAUGGGGCUGUGGUCCAGAACUUGGACCAGUUGUACAUCCCAGUCAGCGAGCAGCACUGGAUCGGCUUCCUCAGCCUGAAGUCAGUGGAGCGCUCUGACGCCGGCCGGUACUGGUGCCAGGUGGAGGAUGGGGGUGAAACCGAGAUCUCCCAGCCAGUGUGGCUCACGGUAGAAGGUGUGCCAUUUUUCACAGUGGAGCCAAAAGAUCUGGCAGUGCCACCCAAUGCCCCUUUCCAACUGUCUUGUGAGGCUGUGGGUCCCCCUGAACCUGUUACCAUUGUCUGGUGGAGAGGAACUACGAAGAUCGGGGGACCCGCUCCCUCUCCAUCUGUUUUAAAUGUAACAGGGGUGACCCAGAGCACCAUGUUUUCCUGUGAAGCUCACAACCUAAAAGGCCUGGCCUCUUCUCGCACAGCCACUGUUCACCUUCAAGCACUGCCUGCAGCCCCCUUCAACAUCACCGUGACAAAGCUUUCCAGCAGCAACGCUAGUGUGGCCUGGAUGCCAGGUGCUGAUGGCCGAGCUCUGCUACAGUCCUGUACAGUUCAGGUGACACAGGCCCCAGGAGGCUGGGAAGUCCUGGCUGUUGUGGUCCCUGUGCCCCCCUUUACCUGCCUGCUCCGGGACCUGGUGCCUGCCACCAACUACAGCCUCAGGGUGCGCUGUGCCAAUGCCUUGGGGCCCUCUCCCUAUGCUGACUGGGUGCCCUUUCAGACCAAGGGUCUAGCCCCAGCCAGCGCUCCCCAAAACCUCCAUGCCAUCCGCACAGAUUCAGGCCUCAUCUUGGAGUGGGAAGAAGUGAUCCCCGAGGCCCCUUUGGAAGGCCCCCUGGGACCCUACAAACUGUCCUGGGUUCAAGACAAUGGAACCCAGGAUGAGCUGACAGUGGAGGGGACCAGGGCCAAUUUGACAGGCUGGGAUCCCCAAAAGGACCUGAUCGUACGUGUGUGCGUCUCCAAUGCAGUUGGCUGUGGACCCUGGAGUCAGCCACUGGUGGUCUCUUCUCAUGACCGUGCAGGCCAGCAGGGCCCUCCUCACAGCCGCACAUCCUGGGUACCUGUGGUCCUUGGUGUGCUAACGGCCCUGGUGACGGCUGCUGCCCUGGCCCUCAUCCUGCUUCGAAAGAGACGGAAAGAGACGCGGUUUGGGCAAGCCUUUGACAGUGUCAUGGCCCGGGGAGAGCCAGCCGUUCACUUCCGGGCAGCCCGGUCCUUCAAUCGAGAAAGGCCCGAGCGCAUCGAGGCCACAUUGGACAGCUUGGGCAUCAGCGAUGAACUAAAGGAAAAACUGGAGGAUGUGCUCAUCCCAGAGCAGCAGUUCACCCUGGGCCGGAUGUUGGGCAAAGGAGAGUUUGGUUCAGUGCGGGAGGCCCAGCUGAAGCAAGAGGAUGGCUCCUUUGUGAAAGUGGCUGUGAAGAUGCUGAAAGCUGACAUCAUUGCCUCAAGCGACAUUGAAGAGUUCCUCAGGGAAGCAGCUUGCAUGAAGGAGUUUGACCAUCCACACGUGGCCAAACUUGUUGGGGUAAGCCUCCGGAGCAGGGCUAAAGGCCGUCUCCCCAUCCCCAUGGUCAUCUUGCCCUUCAUGAAGCAUGGGGACCUGCAUGCCUUCCUGCUCGCCUCCCGGAUUGGGGAGAACCCCUUUAACCUACCCCUCCAGACCCUGAUCCGGUUCAUGGUGGACAUUGCCUGCGGCAUGGAGUACCUGAGCUCUCGGAACUUCAUCCACCGAGACCUGGCUGCUCGGAAUUGCAUGCUGGCAGAGGACAUGACAGUGUGUGUGGCUGACUUCGGACUCUCCCGGAAGAUCUACAGUGGGGACUACUAUCGUCAAGGCUGUGCCUCCAAACUGCCUGUCAAGUGGCUGGCCCUGGAGAGCCUGGCCGACAACCUGUAUACUGUGCAGAGUGACGUGUGGGCGUUCGGGGUGACCAUGUGGGAGAUCAUGACACGUGGGCAGACGCCAUAUGCUGGCAUCGAAAACGCUGAGAUUUACAACUACCUCAUUGGCGGGAACCGCCUGAAACAGCCUCCGGAGUGUAUGGAGGACGUGUAUGAUCUCAUGUACCAGUGCUGGAGUGCUGACCCCAAGCAGCGCCCGAGCUUUACUUGUCUGCGAAUGGAACUGGAGAACAUCUUGGGCCAGCUGUCUGUGCUAUCUGCCAGCCAGGACCCCUUAUACAUCAACAUCGAGAGAGCUGAGGAGCCCACUGCGGGAGGCAGCCUGGAGCUACCUGGCAGGGAUCAGCCCUACAGUGGGGCUGGGGAUGGCAGUGGCAUGGGGGCAGUGGGUGGCACUCCCAGUGACUGUCGGUACAUACUCACCCCCGGAGGGCUGGCUGAGCAGCCAGGGCAGGCAGAGCACCAGCCAGAGAGUCCCCUCAAUGAGACACAGAGGCUUUUGCUGCUGCAGCAAGGGCUACUGCCACACAGUAGCUGUUAGCCCACAGGCAGAGGGCAUCGGGGCCAUUUGGCCGGCUCUGGUGGCCACUGAGCUGGCUGACUAAGCCCCGUCUGACCCCAGCCCAGACAGCAAGGUGUGGAGGCUCCUGUGGUAGUCCUCCCAAGCUGUGCUGGGAAGCCCGGACUGACCAAAUCACCCAAUCCCAGUUCUUCCUGCAACCACUCUGUGGCCAGCCUGGCAUCAGUUUAGGCCUUGGCUUGAUGGAAGUGGGCCAGUCCUGGUUGUCUGAACCCAGGCAGCUGGCAGGAGUGGGGUGGUUAUGUUUCCAUGGUUACCAUGGGUGUGGAUGGCAGUGUGGGGAGGGCAGGUCCAGCUCUGUGGGCCCUACCCUCCUGCUGAGCUGCCCCUGCUGCUUAAGUGCAUGCAUUGAGCUGCCUCCAGCCUGGUGGCCCAGCUAUUACCACACUUGGGGUUUAAAUAUCCAGGUGUGCCCCUCCAAGUCACAAAGAGAUGUCCUUGUAAUAUUCCCUUUUAGGUGAGGGUUGGUAAGGGGUUGGUAUCUCAGGUCUGAAUCUUCACCAUCUUUCUGAUUCCGCACCCUGCCUACGCCAGGAGAAGUUGAGGGGAGCAUGCUUCCCUGCAGCUGACCGGGUCACACAAAGGCAUGCUGGAGUACCCAGCCUAUCAGGUGCCCCUCUUCCAAAGGCAGCGUGCCGAGCCAGCAAGAGGAAGGGGUGCUGUGAGGCUUGCCCAGGAGCAAGUGAGGCCGGAGAGGAGUUCAGGAACCCUUCUCCAUACCCACAAUCUGAGCACGCUACCAAAUCUCAAAAUAUCCUAAGACUAACAAAGGCAGCUGUGUCUGAGCCCAACCCUUCUAAACGGUGACCUUUAGUGCCAACUUCCCCUCUAACUGGACAGCCUCUUCUGUCCCAAGUCUCCAGAGAGAAAUCAGGCCUGAUGAGGGGGAAUUCCUGGAACCUGGACCCCAGCCUUGGUGGGGGAGCCUCUGGAAUGCAUGGGGCGGGUCCUAGCUGUUAGGGACAUUUCCAAGCUGUUAGUUGCUGUUUAAAAUAGAAAUAAAAUUGAAGACUAAAGACCUAAGGUUUUGUCUCUUUUUUUUUUUCUUUUUUUUUGAGACAGUCUCACUGUGUUGCCCAGGCUGGAGUGCAUGGUGUGAUCUUGGUUCACUGCAACCUCUGCCUCCUGGGUUCAAGCGAUUCUUGUGCCUCAGUCACCAGAGUAGCUGGGAUUACAGGGGCUCACUACCAUGCCCAGGUAAUUUUUGUAUUUUUAGUAGAGAUGUGGUUUCGCCAUGUUGGCCAGGGUGGUCUUGAACUCAUGACCUCAAGUGAUCUGCCUGCCUUGGCCUCCCAAAGUGCUGGGAUUACAGUCCUGAGCCACCACACCUGGCCCCAGCUUUGUCUCUUAAAUGUUUACUUUUUUUGAGAUCACAAAGAUGAAAGAUUUUUAUAGAGAGAAAAGUCUGGAAAGACAUAUGCCAAAAUGUUAACAGCUGUUAUCUUUUUUUUUUUUUUUUUGAGACCGAGUCUCACUCUGUCGCCCAGGCUGGAGUGCAAUUGCGCGAUCUGAGCUCACUGCAAGCUCUGCCUCCCAGGUUCACGCCAUUCUCCUGCCUCAGCCUCCCGAGUAGCUGGGACUACAGGUGCCUGCCACCACGCCCGGCUAAUUUUUUGUAUUUUUAGUAGAGAUAGGGUUUCACCGUAUUAGCCAGGAUGAUCUCAAUCUCCUGACCUCGUGAUCCGCCUGCCUCAGCCUCCCAAAGUGUUGGGAUUACAGGCGUGAGCCACCGCACCUGGCAACAGCUGUUACCUUUAAAUGAUGGGGUUAAGGGGACGUUCUUCUUUGUGCUUUCCAAGUUUUCUGCAUUGAGCACAAAAUGCUUUUGUAAUUAGAUACAGGAUCCCAAUGAAUCUUAUUAUACUGAAGAUAAUACAGAGUCACCGUGGGCAGUUAGAAAAAUGCAAAAAAUCGGCUGGGCGCAGUGGCUCACGCCUGUAAUCCCAGCACUUUGGGAGACCUGGGUGUGUGGAUCACGAGGUCAGAAGUUCAAGACUAGUCUGACCAACAUGGUGACACCCCGUCUUUACUAAAAAUACAAAAAUUAGCUGGGCAUGGUGGCGCGUGUCUGUAAUCCCAGCUACUCAGGACACUGAGGCAGGAGAAUUGCUUGAACUCAGGAGGCGGAGGUUGCAGUGAGUCGAGAUCCCGGCAGCCUAGGUGACAGGCGAGACUCCAUCUCAAAAAUAAAAUAAAAAUAAAAAUGCAAAAAAUAAUAAAAGGUGCCAGUUACCUAUACUCCCACCACCUAGAGAUAAUCACCAUUGAUCUUUUGAAAAUGCAAAUAUUCAGCUGGGCACAGUGGCGUGUAUUUUUUUUUUUUUUUGAGACGGAGUCUCGAGUCUCUCUCUGUCGCCCAGGCUAGAGUGCAGUGGUGUGAUCUCGGCUCACUGUAACCUCUGUCUCCCAGGUUUAAUCAAGUCUCUUGUCUUGGCUUCCCGAGUAGUUGGGACUACAGGCACGAGCCACUGUGUCCGGCUAUUUUUUGUAUUUUUUUGUAGAGACAGGGUUUCGCCAUGUUGGCCAGGCUGGUCUCGAACUCCUGAUUUCAAGUGAUCUGCCUGCCUUAGCCUCCCAAAGUGCUGUGAUAACAGGGGUGAGACACCAUACCCAGCUUGUAAUCCCAGCACUUUGGGAGGCUGAGGCGGGUGGAUCACUUCAGGCCGGGAGUUCGAGACCAGCCUGGGCAACAUGAAACCCCAUCUCAACUAAAAAUUCAAAAAAGUUUAGCCAGGCUUGGUGGCGCAGGUUUGUCAUCUCAGCUACUGGGUGACUGAGGCAUGAGAAUCACUUAAACCUGGGAGGAGGAGGUUGCAGUAAGCUGAGAUCUUGCCACUAAACUUCGGCCUGGGUGACAGAUUAAGACUGUCUCAGAAACAAAACAAAACAACAAAAAAGCUUUUAGAGCAAGUUCAUGGGAGAUGCAGCAGGAGGCGCAGGAACCACACAUGUGCUAGUGAGGAGUGUGGGGAGACUGGGAGGGCCCACAGGUAUUGUGCUGCUUCUGGCUGAGGGCAGGGGAAUAGGGUGGCUGCUUCUGAAAGCAAAUAUCCUGAAAAACCUGUUGCUGGUACUCCAAAUUCUGGUUCCCAUGUAGAUCAUGAAACCUGAAAAACUUCCAGGCAAGUAGCUUUCAGAAUCUUUCCUGCUGUGAUUAGCUUUCACUGCAGGUAGUGAUUACCUGUGAGAUAACAUCUGGGAAUUAUUGAUUGAAAAGACCUUCACUAUCGGUUGGGGGCGGUGGCUGAUGCCUGUAAUCCCAGCACUUUGUGAGGCUGAGGCGGGUGGAUCACCUGAGGUCAGGGGUUCAAGACCAGCCUGGCCAACAUGGUGAAACCCCAUCUCUACUAAAAAAUACAAAAACUAGCCAGGAGUGGUGGCAGGCACCUGUAAUCCCAGCUACUUGGGAGGCUAAGGCAGGAGAAUCACUUGAACCCUGGAGGCGGAGGUUGCAGUGAACUGAGAUGGCACCAGUGCACUCCAGCCUGGGUGACAGAGCGAGACUCCAUCUCAAAAAAAAAAAAAAAAAAAAGAGGCCAGGCAUGGUGGCUCACGCCUAUAAUCCCAGCGCUUUGGGAUUUUCUGUCUCAAAAAAAAAAAGAGAGAGACUCUGGAUCAAAAAGGAUUUUCACAAACAGAUCCAAAGAACCAGCAUCCAGAUUAAGAAACAGCAUUAACAGCAACCCAGAAGCAACCCUUGGGACCUGCCUCAAUCUCUGCCUCCUCCCUACUCCCCAUAGGUAACCUCUAUCCUGACCUCUUAACACCAUGGAUCAGUGAAGCUCCUUUUAAAAGUAUAUAAAUGGAGUCAUGUAGAUUUGAUUACUUUGCGUUUGGCUUCUUUCCCUCAGCAACAUGUUUAUAAGGAUCAUCUAACAACAGCAGUUUUGAAAAGUGAGUCUCAAAGAGGCAAGAAUGGCCGGGCAUGGUGGCUCACACCCGUAAUCCCAGCGCUUUGGGAGGCCGAGGCGGGCGGAUCACAAGGUCAGGAGUUUGAGACCAGCCUGGCUAACAGGGUGAAACCCUGUCUUUACUAAACCCUGUCUUUACUAAAAAUACACAAAAUUAGCCAGGUAUGGUGGCAGGCACGUGUAAUCCUAGCUACUCGGGAGGCUGAGGCAGGAGAAUCACUUGAACCUGGGAGGGGGAGGUUGCAGUGAGCCACUACAUUCCAGCUUGGGUGAGAGAGUGAGACUCCAUCUCGGAAAAAAAAAAAAUUAGCUGGGCGUGCUGGUGGGUGCCUGUAAUCCCAGCUACUUGGGAGGCUGAGGUAGGAGAAUUGCUUGAACCUGGGAGGUGGAAGUUGCUGUGAGACGAGAUUGUGCCAUGGCACUCCAGCCUGGACAAGAGUGAGACUCCAUCUCAAAAAAGAAAAUAAUAAUAAUAUAGUUUAUUUUUCAGUAUUUCAUGUUGAUUUAUCUCAAAUUUAUUGUUGAAUAAGAAGUGAUACAGAGAUUCAAAGUUAUUUUUCCCAGAUACUUUUUAUUGUCCCAAUACCACCAUUUAUUGAACAAUCUAUAUUUUAUGCACAUUUCUUUUUUUUUUCUUUUUUUUGAUACAGGGUCUUGCUCUGUUUCUGCCUGGGCUGGAGUAAAGUGAUAGUAAACUGAUUCUCCCACCUCAGCGUCCUGAAUAGCUGGGACCACAGGCACACGCCACUGCACCUGGCAAAUUUUUAAGUGUUUUUUUUUUUUUUUAAUACAGAGCCUUGCUCUGUCGCCCAGGCUGGAGUGCAGUGGUGUGAUCUCGGCUCACUGCAACCUCCGCCUCUCAGUUCAAGCGAGUCUCCUCCUGCCUCACACUCCCAAUUAGCUGGGACUACAGGCACGUGCCACCACAACAUGCUAAUUUUUUGUAUUUUUAGUAGAGACAGGGUUUCACCAUGUUAGCCAGGAUGGUCUCGAUCUCCUGACCUCGUGAUCUGCCCGCCUCAGCCUCCCAAAGUGCUGGGAUUACAGGCUUCAGCCACCGCGCCCGGCCCAGUUUUUAAGUGUUGUAGAGAUGGAGUCUUGCUUUGUUGCCCAGGCUGGUCUUGAACUCUGGGCUGAAGCGAUCUGCCCACCUUGGCCUCUCAAAGUGCGGAGAUUACAGGUGUGAGCCACCACACCCAGCCAGAAUUUCUUGAAUAAUCUGUCUCCAUUUCUCUAUAUAGCCUCAUUGAUCUAUCUAAACUCCCAUAUCUAUUUUGGUUGCUAGACUGUUCAUCCCAAUUACAUGUGCCAGUGUCACUGCUACACUAAUUGAAUUACUAUAAAUGUAUAAUGUUUUCCUAUA